UUCUAAAGUAGUUAUUUUUUACUUUUAAUGUCCACGUGGUAUUUCUGAAAAACAGACAGGUGUUUAAUUUCUUGAUAACCAAAUAUAGACCUGCACAUCAUGUAGUGUGGUGUGCCCUGACCCAACUUCUUCAGCAAAUACAGCACGUGUGGAGUUUAUUUAUAGUUUGACCUCUAGUCUUCAUUGGCUUGUAGUUUAUUUGGGGCAUAAUUCAUUAGCGUGACGGGCUGUGGUAUUUAAGGGUCAGCUCUGAGGAGAAGGAGAUAGAAGAAGAAGCACUGUUCUGGCGUUUGUGCGCUGCUGUGCUGUGUCCGCACCUGGAUUACUGUGUGUGUGGAGAUGGGCUUGGGUUAGGCAGACCAUAGCAGACGGUAGACUGACAGCAUAGGAACCUUUGGAAUGAAAAGGGGGAUGGCUGUAAUAUAGGAAAGCUUUUAAAGAGGACGUGAUGUGAAUAUAUCAAACAUAGUAAUUAUAGGUACCAUUUAUUGAGUGAUUAUCAUGAGCAUACACCGUUAUUUACGUACAUUAGCUUAUUUAAACCUCACAACAAUACUCUGAGAGUGCUGUUAUUUUGUUUAUACAAGGCAGGCAACUGAGUUUUAAGGUAAGUGGCAAAUUUGGUUAAGAUAAACAAAUUUGGUGAACAAAUUUAAAAAUCUGAAAGCUGGGGAAAUCCUUUACAACAUCUGUCAAGUGGGUCAGAAUAUUUGAAAGAAAUUUUGGAUUCGAAUUCAUUUCCUCCAGAGAUGAUAUAGCAGGGCAAGUAUAAAUUAACACUAGUAUCUUAACAUCCUAAGAUUAGAAGGGACCUUUAUAGCUAUCUAGCAAAGGGUUCGCUAAAUUUAUUAAUUGAAAUUACAUACAUGUCUAAAGAGAAGCUGGGAUUGCAGAGAACAUUUAUUGCCUCCUUGAAAGCCUUUGUUGACAGCAGAAUAUAAAUUCAUUAAAGAGAUUUGUGUUUUUGUUCCUUAAAAUUAUAUUUAAGAUUCCGUGUAUUUUACUGUGAAGUUUCACCAAGGGUCAAUCUGCAUCAAACUGUGGAAUGAACUAAACUAAUUUGCAGAACUUCCAGAGAAACCCAAUACUUUAAAUUUAUCUGUUAGCCAGGGUAUUUUGAAGAGGGGGGGAACCUUUAAUGUGAAUAAAUCUACAUUGGGAAGGAAUGGAAUGUUUGAUUUGAAAUGGGCUACUGAAAUGGAAGAACAGAUUAAUCGUGAACCCAGCCAUUACUUUCCUAUUUCUAAAUUGAGUCAGUUGAAAUAUCUGGGAGGGAGUGAGCAUACAGUAUUUAAAAUGAAUAUAAAUUUAAAAUUAGAAAAGGUUUUGUUGUAGAAAAUAUUUUAAAACAAAUUGAGCAAAAAGGAAAAAUUUGCCAAUUACCAGCCAUUACUGUGAUACAAACAUUGUUGAGAUUCUGGUAUAUACAUUUCUAGCCUUUUUAAAAACCCACAUAUAUGAUAUCAUUGUGUGAAGACUUACGUAUAUAUUCAUAUUAUAAGUUUAAACAAAAGGUUUCUUGAAGGCAAGACUGGUAACUGACCAAUAACUCUUUAUGAAAAACUAUGUAUGUAUGUAUGUGAGUGUGUGUGUGUGUGUGCGUGUGUGUAUAUAUAUAUGCACACAAUCAUAUAUCAGAGGGAACUUGUAAGUUUGCAAUCAUAUAUCAGAGGGAACUUGUAAACAGAACAUGUACAGAAUUUUUACAACUUAAUAAUAAAGAUAAUCCAAUUAAAGAAUGGGCAAAGUAUUUGAAUGGUUAUUUUUCCAAAGAAGGUAUUCAGAUGGUCAAUAAGCACAUUAAAAAUGCUCAACAUCAUUCGUCAUUAGAGAAGUGAAAAUCAAAAUCAUAAUGAGAUACUACUUCACGCCCACCAGAACAGCUAUAAUAAAAAUGACUGAUAAUAACAAGUGUUGAUGAGAAAGUGGAUGAAUUGGAAUCCUCAUACACUGUUGGUGGGAAUGUAAAAUGGUACAGCCACUUUGGUAAAUGUCUCGCAGUUCUUUGAAAGGUUAAACAUAGAGUUACCAGUUAACUCAGCAGUUCGACUCCCAGUUAUCUACCCAAGAGAAAUGAAAACGUAACUCUCUACAAAAACUCAUACAUGACACUAUUUGGUUGAUGGUUACACUAGAGGCCUGGACUUCACCAUUAUAUGAUACAUACAUAUAUCAAAACAGCAUUAAUACCCCCUAGAUUUAUACCAAAAAUAACCCUCGUAUGUGAAUUUUCAUUGCAGCAUUAUUCGUAAUAGCCAAAAAAUGGAAACAACCCAAAUGUCCAUCCGUGAUGAAUGGAUAAACAAAAUGUUUCAUAUCCAUAUGAUGGAAUUUUACCUGGCAAUAAAAAGGAAUGAAGCACUGAUACAUGCCACAACAUUAUGAACCCCAAAAAAUGCUUAAAUGAAAGAGGCCAGUCACAGAAGACCACAUAUUAAUAUGACAUCAUUUAUAUAAAAUGUCCAGAAUAGUUAAAUCUAUACAUAGAGAAAUUAAAUCAGUGUUUGGGGGAAGGGGGUAAGGUCCAGAUAUGGAGGUGCGAUUGGUGACGGGUACAGGGUUCUUUCUGGGGUGCUGAAAAUGAUGGUGAUGGUCACACAACUUUGUAAAUAUGCUAAAAAGCAGUGACCGUAUGCUUUGAAAAGGUGAAUCUAUGGUAUGUAAAUUAUAUAUUAAUAAAGCUGUUAAAAAUAUGGUAGCUUAUUUUCUGAGAUUUCCCGGCUCGUUCCCCAUUUCUGUUUUAUGUGUACCAUCUCUUUUCUUUUUUUUUUCUAUUUUCUCUCUCCUGAUCAAGCCGUUUCUUGUCGGUGUGAGUUCCUGUCUUAGAUGUGAGUCCUGGAGUGUCAGUUUCCAGAGUUUAUACCCUUAGACUUUGCUGUGGGCACUUCUACUCACUAACUGGGAUAGAGAAAAACUUGUGGUUUCAGCUGCUGUGCUCCCAUGGGCAGGCCAUGAUUGACAAUGAGUACCUGUUGGCUGCCUUGUAGAUCUGUUCUCUGGCCUGUCAGUCACCCGGCUGCUUCCCUUUGCAUCCUUCCUCAGAGAUGCCGAGAUUCUGCAAGUCUUGUAUGUAGUUUGUACCAAAGCCACUUUUAUUUUUGGAUUCAAGAGGAUACUUUCUCACCUAAUUUUGUUGUAAAUGUUGUCCAUGGGUUUUGGUUUUGAUAUCAGUUGUUCUGUUUUUGUGUGGAGAUUUGGGAAAAUCAAACAAUUUUGCUUCCAUUGCUGUGGCCAUCUUCCUAGAAUUCAGAAGUGUAAUCUUUCCGGCUGUUUGAGGAAGAGAUUUGGAGGGAAUUGAUCUGACAAAAACAGAAGAUAUUGUCCUGGAGAUUUUAAUGUCCUUGAAAGAACUCUUGGUCUAUUAGUCUAUUUAAAUCUGUUUAAACUCAGAACCUGGCAUUAGUAAACACUCAGAUAAAUAUUCUUGGAAUGCUGUUGAGUUUGUUGAACGUAGAUGUGCAGGAGAUGAAUGGCUACCUGAAUGAGGUGGGCUAGAAUUUAGAGCUGGUACCCACUUACCAGUAUGGUCAUUGAGGGGGCUGGAUGAAUAGUUUCUCCUCCUUAUGCAUGCAGAUCGGAAACACUUCUGAAGCUUUGGUCAGCUUGUCUCACAUGCCUCAGUUUAUCACGAAUGCCUGAAAUGAUACAUAACUAUCAUGUUAAGUUUCGGUCUCACUAGGGUAUGAAUACUAGGGUGUUGAUCAGAAUGAUGCAGAUCCUACAUGCAUCUGAAUGAGUGUGCUAGAGACCCUUAAUUAAUCCUUAGGUGCUGGGUCUGUUUUCCAAGUCCAAGGCUUUGGAUUCCGUUUUUGUACAUUAAACUACCAUAAACCCUGCUUGUGGGUAACCAAAGCACAUGUAGUGGUUUAAUCAUGCAGGACCUUUCCAAUUUGGUAUGGAGGGAACUGCCUGAUCUUUCCUGAGCUCUCUUUUCUCUAAUAAUCACUUUUGUUUAUUCUACUCUUACAUGAAUCGUAAAAUGUUAGUAAAUAGAACUAUAUAUGUUAUAGAGAUGAAUUCCCUAAAGGCCCCCUCGAUGACAACACUGUGAUGUGUGCUCCAUCCUUCUCGAUCCUCUUAUCCUCACCAACACUUAGCGUCAGAGGUUUCAUUUGCUUGGUGCUCUGUUUUGCAACAUGUCCUUGGAGAAAAGGUUGCUGAGGUUGAAAUGAAGGACAAAACCAUGCAAUGUGCCGUCUGUUGAAGACAGCAUAUUCUUUUGUGUUUUAACAAAGGCCUGCAAUGCUUUAAUUAGAAGAAGUUGAAUUGGGUGGCAAUUUAAGUACCUUGGACAUUUUUCAAAUCUGGGUGAUGCCCAGUGAUCUUGGUUUUAAGUAAAGUACGUAAAUAAUAGAAUUAUAAGGAAUCCAGUGUUUACUUUCUGAGUAGCAGUGAAGAGGCUAAGUGUUUUCCUUCUGGGUUGGCUUCUCAGAUGUGUUUCUCAAUAAAUUCUCUAGAGAUAUGUGUGUCAAGUCAGCUUGUUAAAAAACAAAGAAACAUGAAGGCAUGUAGCCCUCACAGUUGGAUGCUUUUAAACACUGCAGCUGUUUGAAAGGCCGGAGCGAACGAAUUCAAUUAUGACUGAGAAACCUAUCAUCUCUCCCUGUUAGUGCUUGUCAUGAACAUCCUUCUCAAAAUAAUGGUAGCCCAGGGAAGAGAGUUGUGCAAGGAAUAUAGACAGCUUCAGUUAACUUCAAUUUAAAAAGGAACAAAAGACAAAAAAUAAAAUGACACUUAAUUCUUAAAAGAUAAGUGAAGGAUUAUAAUCUUGGUUCACCAUGCUAGAAGUUUACUCAAACUUCCAUUUUUUUGGGUCUACUCUUUGAAACUGUGCUUUAUUUUGUACAUAGUGGUUAAUUUAACUCUUUAAACAAAUGAGUUCUUGGCUUAAAGCUUUUCUGCAUUAUUAUUUACAACCUUUUUUUGGUAAUAAAAGAUGAUCAUGGUAAAGUUUAUGCAAUAGAAAAAUAUAAAAAGUUAAAACAAAAAGAAAAAUAACUUCCCUUUCAAUUUUUCAUCCUUUCAGGAAGUUAUAGAUUGAUGCAUACCCUAGACUUUAAAAAUUCAUAUGACCAGGCGCAGUGGCUCACGCCUGUAAUCUUAGCACUUUGGGAGGCCAAGGCGGGCAUAUUGCCUGAACUCAGGAGUUCGAGACCAGCCUGGGCAACAUGGUGAAACCUUGUCUCUACUAAAAUACAAAAGAAAUUAGCUGGGUAUGGCAGCGUGCACCUGUAGUCCCAGCUACUCGGGAGGCUGAGGCAGGAGAAUUGCUUGAACCCGGGAGGCGGAGGUUGCAGUGAGCCGAGAUUGCACCACUGCACUCCAGCCGGGUGACAGAGCGAGACUCCAUCUCUCCAAAAAAAAAAAAAAAAGCAUAUAUACAUGUAUAUAUACACACAGACGUACCUAUAAUUUGUUGUGAUGUAUGAAUUGCAUUUUUUUGCAAAAAUUAUAUGUUUACUAUUCUGCGACAUGGUUUGUUUCACCUAACAGGUCAUAGUCUUCUCUCCAUAUAGCUGAGAUCUGGUGAGCUGUAUUCUCCCUUUUUGUGUCAGUAAGGGUAUUACAUACAUAAUGACCCAUACAUAAGAAAGAUGUCAGGGGAAACUGCAACCCUACCCAAAUAGUUUGUCCUUCUCAACCCCUGGCCCACAUAGAUGUGCAGUACCUAAAAGUCAUUUAACAGCUGUCAAAUCAAUUGCACGGCUGCUGGUGUCAUAGAGGAUAAGCAGCAGCUGGUGGGCAAGUGUAACCAUCCCCAUUUCUCUGCAUGGGUGGAGGGGGGACAGCAGCAGAUGGACAUAGUUCUACUCUUGUUCAAUUUUUAACUGUAACUUAAGGGCUUUCCUUUAGGUGUUUAAUUUUAAAGUAAUAAAAAGUGAUUUUAGUGAAAUACUUAAAAAAAGAUUUAGAUAAGUUAGAAGAAAAGAAUUAUCCGUAGUCCCUCGCUACCCAAAUAUAAUUAUUGUUAGCAUUCUGUGAUACUUCUUUUUGUUCAUGCCUUUUCUUGAAUCUGUUGUUAGAAAUGGCACUUUACAUCUGUGGUCUUCCUCCCUAAAACCCAUCACUCAGUCUAAUCAUGAGAAAAACAUCAGAUAAAUCCUGACUAAGAAACUUUUAAAAAAAAUGCCUCUUGAGAACCCCUCAAAACUGUCACAGUCAUUAAAAACAAUGAACGUCUGAGAAACUGUCACAGCCAAGAGGAGCUUAGGGAGACAUAUGACUAAAUGUAAUGUGUUGUCCUAGAUGGGAUUCUGAAACAGAAAAAGGACAUUUGGGUGUCCAUACUGAAGAGGGAUGUUAACAAUAGAAGAAACUGGGUGUGAUUUAUAAGGAAACUUUUUCAACUAUCUUCACCUUUUCUGUAAAUCUAAAACUAUUCUGAAAUAAGGUCAAAUACAUCUUUUAAAAAGUACUACAAUAAUACUAUGUAUGCAGUUUUGAACUCUGCUUUUUCUUACUGCGCCAUCUUUUUAAAAAAUCUAGUGAUUGUUCACUAUUUCUCAGAAUGAAUAUGCUUUGAUUCACGUAACUAUUGCCUUUGCUGGGGAGAUGUGUGUGUGUGUGUGUGUGUGUGUAUGUAUAUAUAUCCCCCCUACAAAAGCCUAUUCUAAUUUACAGUUACACCACCUAUAUAUAUAAAUACCUGAUUUCCUUGAACUUUCUCUAGCAUUGUGUAUAAUCUUUUAUAUCAUAAUCUUUCCCAAAACUAGUAUCUUGAUUUAAUCUGUAUUUCUUUAAUGAAGUUCACAUGUAAGCAUUUCUCCAUUAGGUUUAUUUUACUGCUUCUCUUAAGAAGUCUCUGUUCACAUUAAUUGUCCCACUUGAGCCUGUGUUUUUCUUGUGAGUUUUCUUGAGCUGUUUAAAUAGUAAACACAAAACUUUUAAUAGUAAGCACAAACAGAGAUGGGAAAUUGGACUUAAUAAGUAUUCUUUUGUAAUGAUCCUGUAGAAUGCAACUAGGAAGAGGAAAAAUUAUAAUUUAUUAAGAUAAAAACUAAUGUAAUUGAAAUUCAUAUCAAAAGAAAAUACAGAAUGAUAGUAAGGAGUAGCUCAUUUUCUUUGUAUUUGCUUUAUUUUGGAGCAGCAUGUGUAUUUUGGAAAUGUUGGGGUUGUUUAACAAAAUUGUUUAUACUUCCUGCGUUUAUUUUUUAAGGUAUUUGCUAGAUCAAAAAUAAUACAUUUUGUAACUACCUGUUAACAUACAAGAAUAUCUCAAAACAUUUAGAAUGUAAUUUCUUUAAGCAAUAUGAAUAGAGCCUACAAUUAAAAUAUUUUGUUUAGUAAUAAUGAAAAACUAGUUGUUAGCAAGUGAUUUUGUUGCUAGCUGCGAAACUAGAACUAAUAAUUAUCUUAAUCCUUUCUCCCCUGCAAAAACCCCACACACUUUUCCCCUAAAAAUAAAGAAAGUCAUGUUGUGAAGUAGAGGAUCCGGUGGAAUUAAAAAUGCAUUGACCCAGGAUCUCCUGGUACCUGGCCAUGGACAGGAGUAGGUCUUUAUCCAUGGGUGAAAGGCAGUUCAGUCUGCUGGUUUGGUUUAUUUUAGCCCUGCAUGCCUGAAACAGACUCUUGAGAGAGGGGCCCAGGAGCACGGGGGCUGCAUGUUCUUUCCCCAUGACUGCAAAUGCCAGAGAUACUGUGAAACUGGACUGUGGAACUCAUUAACCCGGGCCUGAUGGCUGGCAGGCUUCACAGCUUCCUCUGAUUUUGACAGGGGAUGGAAGAUGUUCAGACACCUUGUGUUCCUGAUGUUAUUAGCAGCAUAAGGCAAUUAUCUAAAGCGGCCAUGAAAGAGGAUGCCAAACCCAGCAAAGAUAAUGAGGACGCCUUUUACAACUCUCAGAAGUUCGAAGUCCUGUACUGUGGAAAGGUGACCGUGACCCACAAGAAGGCCCCCUCAAGCCUCAUCGAUGACUGCAUGGAGAAGUUCAGCCUGCACGAACAGCAGCGCCUGAAGAUCCAAGGGGAGCAGCGCGGUCCGGACCCAGGAGAGGACCUGGCUGACUUGGAGGUGGUGGUGCCCGGGUCCCCCGGAGACUGCCUGCCGGAGGAGGCUGACGGCACCGACACCCACCUUGGCUUACCUGCCGGGGCCAGCCAGCCUGCCCUGACCAGCUCUCGGGUCUGCUUCCCUGAGCGGAUUUUGGAAGAUUCUGGCUUUGAUGAGCAGCAGGAGUUUCGGUCUCGGUGCAGCAGUGUCACCGGCGUGCAACGGAGAGUUCACGAGGGCAGCCAGAAAUCCCAGCCGCGACGGAGACACGCGAGCGCACCCAGUCACGUCCAGCCCUCGGACUCGGAGAAGAACAGGACCAUGCUCUUCCAGGUUGGGCGAUUUGAGAUUAACCUUAUCAGUCCAGACACUAAAUCAGUUGUGCUAGAAAAGAAUUUUAAAGAUAUCUCCUCUUGUUCUCAGGGUAUAAAGCAUGUGGAUCACUUUGGCUUUAUCUGCCGGGAGUCUCCAGAGCCUGGACUUAGCCAGUAUAUUUGUUAUGUAUUCCAGUGUGCCAGCGAAUCUCUGGUUGAUGAGGUAAUGCUGACUCUGAAACAGGCCUUCAGUACGGCGGCUGCCCUGCAGAGUGCCAAGACGCAGAUUAAACUGUGUGAGGCCUGCCCGAUGCACUCUUUGCAUAAGCUCUGUGAAAGGAUUGAAGGUCUCUACCCACCAAGAGCCAAGCUGGUGAUACAGAGGCAUCUCUCAUCACUGACAGAUAAUGAGCAAGCUGACAUCUUUGAAAGAGUUCAGAAAAUGAAGCCAGUCAGUGACCAGGAAGAAAAUGAACUUGUGAUUUUACACCUGAGGCAGCUGUGUGAAGCCAAGCAGAAGACACACGUGCACAUCGGGGAAGGCCCUUCUACUAUUUCAAAUAGUACAAUCCCAGAAAAUGCAACAAGCAGUGGAAGGUUCAAACUUGACAUUCUGAAAAAUAAAGCUAAGAGAUCCUUAACUAGCUCCCUGGAAAAUAUCUUCUCAAGGGGAGCUAACAGAAUGAGAGGUCGGCUUGGAAGUGUGGACAGUUUUGAACGGUCCAACAGUCUUGCUUCAGAGAAGGACUACUCACCAGGGGAUUCUCCACCAGGGACACCGCCAGCGUCCCCACCGUCCUCAGCUUGGCAAACGUUUCCCGAAGAGGAUUCCGACUCCCCGCAGUUUCGAAGACGGGCACACACGUUCAGCCACCCACCUUCAAGCACAAAGAGAAAGCUGAAUUUGCAGGAUGGGAGGGCUCAGGGUGUGCGUUCCCCUCUGCUGAGGCAGAGCUCCAGUGAACAGUGCAGCAAUCUUUCGUCAGUUCGACGCAUGUACAAGGAGAGUAAUUCUUCCUCCAGUCUUCCAAGUCUUCACACUUCCUUCUCUGCCCCUUCCUUCACUGCCCCCUCUUUCCUGAAAAGCUUUUACCAGAAUUCAGGUAGACUGUCCCCACAGUAUGAAAAUGAAAUCAGACAAGACACUGCUUCAGAAUCAAGUGAUGGAGAAGGGAGAAAAAGGACCUCAUCUACCUGCAGCAAUGAGUCCCUAAGUGUGGGAGGAACCUCUGUCACUCCUCGCCGGAUCUCCUGGCGGCAGCGCAUUUUCCUCAGGGUUGCUUCUCCCAUGAACAAAUCUCCCUCAGCAAUGCAACAGCAAGAUGGAUUGGACAGGAACGAGCUGCUGCCACUGUCCCCCCUCUCUCCAACCAUGGAGGAGGAACCGCUGGUUGUAUUCCUGUCUGGGGAGGAUGACCCAGAAAAGAUUGAAGAAAGAAAGAAAUCAAAAGAACUGAGGAGCUUGUGGAGAAAAGCUAUACACCAACAAAUCUUGUUACUUCGAAUGGAAAAAGAAAACCAGAAACUUGAAGCAAGCAGAGAUGAACUCCAGUCCAGAAAAGUUAAAUUAGACUAUGAAGAAGUUGGUGCAUGUCAGAAAGAGGUCUUAAUAACUUGGGAUAAGAAGUUGUUAAACUGCAGAGCUAAAAUCAGAUGUGAUAUGGAAGAUAUUCAUACUCUUCUUAAAGAAGGAGUUCCCAAAAGUCGACGAGGAGAAAUUUGGCAGUUUCUGGCUUUACAGUACCGACUCAGACACAGAUUGCCUAAUAAACAACAGCCUCCUGACAUAUCCUAUAAGGAACUUUUGAAGCAGCUCACUGCUCAGCAGCAUGCGAUUCUCGUGGAUUUAGGAAGGACGUUUCCUACUCACCCUUACUUUUCAGUACAGCUUGGGCCAGGACAGCUGUCACUGUUUAACCUCCUGAAAGCCUAUUCUUUGCUGGACAAAGAAGUGGGAUACUGUCAGGGGAUCAGCUUUGUGGCUGGAGUCCUGCUUCUGCACAUGAGUGAAGAGCAAGCCUUUGAAAUGCUGAAAUUCCUCAUGUAUGACCUCGGCUUCCGCAAGCAGUACAGACCUGACAUGAUGUCGCUGCAGAUUCAAAUGUACCAGCUGUCCAGGCUCCUUCAUGACUAUCACAGAGAUCUCUACAAUCACCUUGAAGAAAAUGAAAUCAGCCCCAGUCUUUAUGCUGCCCCCUGGUUCCUCACAUUGUUUGCCUCUCAGUUUUCAUUAGGAUUUGUAGCCAGAGUUUUUGAUAUUAUUUUUCUUCAGGGAACUGAAGUUAUAUUCAAGGUUGCACUCAGCCUACUGAGCAGCCAAGAGACACUUAUAAUGGAAUGUGAGAGCUUUGAAAAUAUUGUUGAGUUUCUUAAAAACACGCUACCUGAUAUGAAUACCUCUGAAAUGGAAAAAAUUAUUACCCAGGUUUUUGAGAUGGAUAUUUCUAAGCAGUUGCAUGCCUAUGAGGUGGAAUAUCAUGUGCUACAGGAUGAGCUUCAGGAAUCUUCAUAUUCCUGUGAGGAUAGUGAAACUUUGGAGAAGCUGGAGAGGGCCAAUAGCCAACUGAAAAGACAAAACAUGGACCUCCUAGAAAAAUUACAGGUAGCUCAUACUAAAAUCCAGGCCUUGGAAUCAAACCUGGAAAAUCUUUUGACGAGAGAGACCAAAAUGAAGUCUUUAAUCCGGACCCUGGAACAAGAAAAAAUGGCUUAUCAAAAGACAGUGGAGCAACUCCGGAAGCUGCUGCCCGCGGAUGCUCUAGUCAAUUGUGACCUGUUGCUGAGAGACCUAAACUGCAACCCUAACAACAAAGCCAAGAUAGGAAAUAAGCCAUAAUUGAAGAGGCACGGCCUCAGCAGAAAGUGCUCCUUAGAAUACUACAGAGAGGAAGAGCCUGCAUGUCGCUGGCCCAAGGCUGGACCCUGAAGCUGAUGGAACCACCUAAUACUGGUGCUGAGCGCCUAGUCACAGCAGGUGGACCUCGUGCUCAUCAGAGCAUGCCAAUCCUAAGCCAUUGGACAUAUGUAGACUGGUUUUUGUUGUUGCUAUGUACAUAUAAAUAUAUAUAUAAAAUGAACAUAGUUCAUGCUUUCAGAUAAAAUGAGUAGAUGUAUAUUUAGAUUAAUUUUUUUAGUCAGAACUUCAUGAAAUCCACACCAAAGGAAAGGUAAACUGAAAUUUCCCUUGGACAUAUGUGAAAUCUUUUUGUCUUUAUAGUGAAACAAAGCCAGAGCAUCUUUGUAUAUUGCAAUAUACUUGAAAAAAAUGAAUGUAUUUUUUUCUCCAAAGAACAGCAUGUUUCACUCAAUGGUGAAAAGGUGGAAACAUUUAUGUAACUUUAUGUGUAUCUGUCUUGAUAUCUACUGACAUUGUCUAUAUGAGGAAAAUGAUUACUGGUCAUGCUCCUGUGAGUUUUUUGGGAAGGUAGGGUCAUUUCUCCCUGCCUGCUUUGUGCCAACUAGCAUGUUGCAUCUACAUGCAUUAUGAGUCUGGUUAGGCAUUACUUUAAACAUACAUAAAGAGACAGUAGGACAUUGUGGCUGAGUCUACCCAGCUCAAGGUAAAGGAGAAUGUUGCUAAUUUUUUAGCAAACUAGACCAGCAUUAUUACUCAAACUAAAAAUAUCACACCUGAAAAAUUUAAUUUAGGACCUAAAAUGUCUAGAUUAGCUUUCUGCUUUUUUUAUUUGAAUAACUCAUUCAGUUGUGAAUGAAUUCCUCUUUAUUUGGUGCCACAGUCACCAAAUGACAAGGAUUUGCCACUUUCCCACCAAAUUGUGAGUGCUUGUAAUUUAGGUCUCUCUACCUUAAAUUCAGUAUAAGGAAACGUAAUUAUGAUUGAUUUUUUCCAAAGAUGACAAGCUGUGUUGAAAUACAUUUUUUCUUUUGACCAAUUGACAGAAUCUAAUAAGCUUUAAUAAUCUUCCCCUUUUAUGUGAAAAGUUUUGAGAACUGUGAAAUGUUUAGGAACAAACUGUUGAAAUCCAUUGGAAGGGAAAAAAGAAAGUGGUACCAGUGUUACCAGCUCAACUAAAACCUGCAAUUCUGCAUUUCAACUCUUCACUUCCUCAGCCUACAAAUAGCUCAUUAGAUGACAUUCACGCAUGCUGGGUAUAGGCAAGGAAAGUAAUUUUCAAAGUACAUUUGCAGUUCUCUUUUUCAGAGAUGAUUCUAUGAUAGUGCCUCUGAAAGUUGAUGCAGCAUUUUUGCCUUUCCAAAAAGUAUUUAUCCUCACUGCUUUUUGCAGUACUUGUAUUUUCACAGAUGGAUUAUCUGGGGUAAUUUUCUUCAAAGGGAGUUUGUUAUACACAGUGAAAAUGUAUUAUAGAGUAGAAUAGUAAAGCUCUAGGGGUUUCAGAAAGCUUUGAUGAACAGAUGACAAACAUCUGAAACCCCCUCCGCACUGUUACCCAGUGUGUAUAUAAUGACUUGUUAUAGCUCAGUGUGCCCUUGAAUCCAUACAGUUUCUUAAAAGACAAUAAAAUCUUAUUAAUAAAGUUAAUGUAACUUCUAAGUUCUAGAAAAUGCUGAUUCUGUCUGCCCCAUUCAAUUGGGGGCUACUAAUUGAUUUGUUGCUUGGAUUUCCUGAGAAUUUCUCUAUUUGUAGGAGGGGUUUUUUCUUUUUACGGUCUGUUGAUGACAAUUACUUUAUGGGUGUGAUGCACCGAUGGUAGCCAAGGAAUCUGUUGGGGAAGUUCGGAAAGAAACCUUUUCUUUCUUUUAUUCAGUUUAAAGUAAACUUUAUCCUGGAUGUUUAGAAUCAACAUUAAGAGUUAUAUUAUGGUGUUCAGAGAUUAAGCUGACUUGGAUACAAUAUUUUCUUUUGAAAAUGAAUUUUCUUUUUCAUUUGUGAUUUUUAAAAAAUGUUGCACCAGUUAUGCUUCAUGCAUCGUUACAUCUUCAUCAGGUUAAUGUAAUGUCUAGUUCCUUUGCAAUAAAUAUAUUGCUGCAGCUUUCUUGACGUAUACUGUUACUUUUCGGGAGAGAAGCAGCUCUUGGUUAGAGUCUUUUACUGCAGGGGUCCCUGGGUACCUGUCUGUGGCCUGUUAUGAACCAGGCUGCACAGCAGUGGUGGGCAUGCGAGCAAGCAUGACUGCCUGAGCUCUGACUCCUGUCAGAUCAGCCACGGCAUUAGAUUCUCAUAGGAGCGCAAACCCUAUUGUGAACUGUGCAUGCAGGAGAUCUAUGUUUUGUGUUCCUUAAGAGAAUCGAAUGCCUGAUGAUCUGUCACUGUCUCCCAUCAUCCCCAGAUGGGAUCGUCUAGUUGCAGGAAAACAGUCAGGGUUCCCACUAAUUCUACAUUAUGGUGAGUAUAUAAUAAUAAUAUGGUGAGGAUAUAAUAAUAAUAAUAGAAAUAAAGUGCACAAUAAAUGUGCUUGAAUCAUUGAAUCAUCCUGAAACCAUCCCCUGCCACCAGUCUGUGGAAAGAUUGUCUUCCAUGAAACCAGUCCCUGGUGUCAAGAAGGUUGAAGACCGCUGCUUUACAAGAUCUGCAUGGUGAAACCCCAUCUCUAGGGAAAAUACAAAAAUUAGCCAGGCGUGGUGGUGUGCAUCUGUAAUCUCAGCUACUCAGGAGAGUAGGAGAGGCAUAUAUUGCUACUUAUAGGAGGCUGGAGAAUAGUUUGAACCUGGGAGGCGGAGCUUGCAGUGAGCUUGCAGUGAGCCAUCAUGCCACUGCACUCUAGCCUGGGCCACAGAGUGAGACUUUGACAAAAAAAAAGAAAAACAAACAACCAAACAAAAAAGAUCUGCAUGGUUUGGAUUGUACCUACUUAAAAUUGCUACACAAAUAAUUCUUCCUAAUAGAGUCAGACAACAAAGAUAAUUUAGGAGACAUUUAUGUAAGUACAUUGUUACCAUUUUUCAACUUACUUUCUCAAUGGAGACUUUUGAAAGAAAAAUAUAAGCAACCACAUUGACAGAUUUGCAUUCUACCCUUUUAUUUUCCAGGCCCCCUCAUAGAUAGCAAGGGAGAGAGAGCCACAAGAAAAUACAAAAUUUUCCAACUGGACGCAGAUAAUUAAGAAUUAAGGACAUUUACUGAUGGAUGUGAUAUGAAUGUUUUUAUAUAAAAUAUGCAUCUCUUGGAGUAUUCUCAUGUAUAUUUGUAAUCCAAUAAAAAUACA